GGCGGCGGAGUCUCCCAAGUCCCCGCCGGGCGGGCGCGCGCCAGUGGACGCGGGUGCACGACUGACGCGGCCCGGGCGGCGGGGCGGGGGCUUGGGACCCCCGAGAGGGGCGGGGACUCCGCGACUCCUCGCUGCCGGGCUCGGCCUGGCGGGUGGGUCGGCGAGCCGGGCGUGGGACUGCCCCGGGCGCGGGCGCUGGUGGCCGGGGCGCGGGACUCCAGACGCCCCGGGGAGCCCCGAGGCCCUGGAACUGCGGCGCUCGGCGAGUCGAUCCGGGAUCGAUAGCAGCUCCAUGUCUCCGGCCUCUGAGGCCCCGCCGGCCGGCUGGGCAGUCCGGGGAGGCCUGGCGGGCGGCGCGUAGGCGGCGGCUGCGGGCGCCGGGGCGCACUAGCGGACGGCGUGGGCGCGCGGCCAGGCGCCUCCCCGGCCCCCGCGACCCAACUCCAGCCCGGGCCGGAAUAAGUUGCUGCCGCCGGCGGAGAGCGGGGCUGCGGAGCCACCGGGGCGCCAUGCCGGCGGUCAAGAAGGAGUUCCCGGGCCGCGAGGACCUGGCCCUGGCUCUGGCCACGUUCCACCCGACCCUGGCCGCGCUGCCGCUGCCGCCGCUGCCAGGCUACCUGGCGCCACUGCCCGCGGCGGCCGCCCUCCCCCCGGCCGCCUCGCUGCCCGCCUCGGCCGCCGGUUACGAGGCUCUGCUGGCCCCGCCGCUCCGCCCCCCGCGCGCCUACCUCAGCCUGCACGAGGCCGCCCCGCACCUCCACCUGCCCAGGGACCCGCUGGCCCUCGAGCGCUUCUCGGCCACCGCGGCCGCGGCCCCGGAUUUCCAGCCGCUGCUGGACAACGGCGAGCCGUGCAUCGAGGUGGAGUGCGGCGCCAACCGCGCGCUGCUCUACGUGCGCAAACUCUGCCAGGGCAGCAAGGGCCCGUCCAUCCGCCACCGCGGCGAGUGGCUCACGCCCAACGAGUUCCAGUUCGUCAGCGGCCGCGAGACGGCCAAGGACUGGAAGCGCAGCAUCCGCCACAAAGGGAAAAGUCUGAAGACGCUUAUGUCCAAGGGGAUCCUGCAGGUGCAUCCUCCGAUCUGCGACUGCCCGGGCUGCCGAAUAUCCUCCCCGGUGAACCGGGGGCGGCUGGCAGACAAGAGGACAGUCGCCCUGCCUGCCGCCCGGAACCUGAAGAAGGAGCGAACUCCCAGCUUCUCUGCCAGCGAUGGUGACAGCGACGGGAGUGGCCCCACCUGUGGGCGGCGGCCAGGCUUGAAGCAGGAGGAUGGUCCGCACAUCCGUAUCAUGAAGAGAAGAGUCCACACCCACUGGGACGUGAACAUCUCUUUCCGAGAGGCGUCCUGCAGCCAGGACGGCAACCUUCCCACCCUCAUAUCCAGCGUCCACCGCAGCCGCCACCUCGUUAUGCCCGAGCAUCAGAGCCGCUGUGAAUUCCAGAGAGGCAGCCUGGAGAUUGGCCUGCGACCCGCCGGUGACCUGUUGGGCAAGAGGCUGGGCCGCUCCCCCCGUAUCAGCAGCGACUGCUUUUCAGAGAAGAGGGCACGAAGCGAAUCGCCUCAAGCAGAGGCGCUGCUGCUGCCGCGGGAGCUGGGGCCCAGCAUGGCCCCGGAGGACCAUUACCGCCGGCUUGUGUCAGCACUGAGCGAGGCCAGCACCUUUGAGGACCCUCAGCGCCUCUACCACCUGGGCCUCCCCAGCCACGAUCUCCUGAGGGUCCGGCAGGAGGUGGCGGCUGCAGCUCUGAGGGGCCCCAGUGGCCUGGAAGCCCACCUGCCCUCCUCCACGGCAGGUCAGCGUCGGAAGCAGGGCCUGGCUCAGCACCGGGAGGGCGCCGCCCCAGCUGCCGCCCCGUCCUUCUCGGAGAGGGAGCUGCCUCAGCCGCCCCCCUUGCUGUCGCCGCAGAAUGCCCCUCACGUCGCCCUGGGCCCCCAUCUCAGGCCCCCCUUCCUGGGGGUGCCCUCGGCUCUGUGCCAGACCCCAGGCUACGGCUUCCUGCCCCCCGCGCAGGCGGAGAUGUUCGCCUGGCAGCAGGAGCUCCUGCGGAAGCAGAACCUGGCCCGGCUGGAGCUGCCCGCCGACCUCCUGCGGCAGAAGGAGCUGGAGAGCGCGCGCCCACAGCUGCUGGCGCCCGAGACCGCCCUGCGCCCCAACGACGGCGCCGAGGAGCUGCAGCGGCGCGGGGCCCUGCUGGUGCUGAACCACGGCGCGGCGCCACUGCUGGCCCUGCCCCCCCAGGGGCCCCCGGGCUCCGGACCCCCCACCCCGUCCCGGGACUCUGCCCGGCGAGCCCCCCGGAAGGGGGGUCCCGGCCCUGCCUCAGCGCGGCCCAGCGAGUCCAAGGAGAUGACGGGGGCUAGGCUCUGGGCACAAGAUGGCUCGGAAGACGAGCCCCCCAAAGACUCGGACGGAGAGGACCCCGAGACGGCAGCUGUUGGGUGCAGGGGGCCCACUCCGGGCCAAGCUCCAGCUGGAGGGGCCGGCGCCGAGGGGAAGGGGCUUUUCCCAGGGUCCACACUGCCCCUGGGCUUCCCUUAUGCCGUCAGCCCCUACUUCCACACAGGCGCGGUAGGGGGACUCUCCAUGGAUGGGGAGGAGGCCCCAGCCCCUGAGGACGUCACCAAGUGGACCGUGGAUGACGUCUGCAGCUUCGUGGGGGGCCUGUCUGGCUGUGGAGAGUACACUCGGGUCUUCAGGGAGCAGGGGAUCGACGGGGAGACCCUGCCACUGCUGACGGAGGAGCACCUGCUGACCAACAUGGGGCUGAAGCUGGGGCCCGCCCUCAAGAUCCGGGCCCAGGUGGCCAGGCGCCUGGGCCGAGUUUUCUACGUGGCCAGCUUCCCCGUGGCUCUGCCACUGCAGCCACCAACCCUGCGGGCCCCGGAGCGAGAACUCGGCACAGGAGAGCAGCCCUUGUCCCCCACGACGGCCACGUCCCCCUAUGGAGGGGGCCACGCCCUUGCCGGUCAAACUUCACCCAAGCAGGAGAAUGGGACCUUGGCUCUACUUCCAGGGGCCCCCGACCCUUCCCAGCCUCUGUGUUGAGGUUGCCGGGGGUAGGGGUGGGGCCACACAAAUCUCCAGGAGCCACCACUCAACACAAUGGCCCUGCCUCCCACCGCUUUAUUUCUUUCGGUUUCGGAUGCAAAACAAAAAAUUUUAAAAGAAAAUGUGACUUCAAAGGAAAGGAACAAAUUUUCAAAGACUUGGGGGAGUGAAGGCAGAGCCUGGUGCAGAUGGACGAGGUCUGCAGACGGAGGGCAGAGGUGGUGGAAGGGGCCAGGGGCCUGCAGGCCUCCCCCUGGAACUGGGACUGGUCUCGGUCUGCUGACGUCAGGGUCAGCUCCCCCGCGGAGCUGACUUCAGCAGCCCACAGCUGUGGGGCUUCAGCAGCCACACCAGCCCAGCCCAGCCCAGCUCUCGAUACGUUUGGUCUUUCAUGCUGAAAAAUAAAUAAUAAAGCCUG